AGCGGUCGCAUGCAGCUCCUAUGAGGCCCCUGCCGCCGGUCGGCGAUGUCCGGCUGGAGCUGUCGCCUCCGCCGCCGCUGCUGCCGGUGCCGGUUGUGAGCGGGUCUCCAGUCGGCUCCUCUGGGCGUCUCAUGGCCUCUAGCAGCUCCCUGGUGCCCGACCGGCUGCGCCUGCCGCUCUGCUUCCUGGGUGUCUUUGUCUGCUAUUUUUACUAUGGGAUCCUGCAGGAAAAGAUGACCCGAGUCGGCCCCCUUUUGGUACUCCCAGAUGCUUGCAAACAACCUAUUCGUCCUCGGCCUUGGUGCCAUAGCCGAAAUACCGUCUCCUCCUGCCUGGGAACAAGAGGAAAGUAUGGGGAAGGAGCCAAGCAGGAGACGUUCACCUUUGCCUUAACUUUGGUCUUCAUUCAAUGUGUGAUCAAUGCUGUGUUUGCCAAGAUCUUGAUCCAGUUUUUUGACACUGCCAGGGUGGAUCGUACCCGGAGCUGGCUCUAUGCUGCCUGUUCUAUCUCCUAUCUGGGUGCCAUGGUCUCCAGCAAUUCAGCACUACAGUUUGUCAACUACCCAACUCAGGUCCUUGGUAAAUCCUGCAAGCCAAUCCCAGUCAUGCUCCUUGGGGUGACCCUCUUGAAGAAGAAGUACCCGUUGGCCAAGUACCUGUGUGUGCUGUUAAUUGUGGCUGGAGUGGCCCUUUUCAUGUACAAACCCAAGAAAGUUGUUGGGAUAGAAGAACACACAGUCGGCUAUGGAGAGCUACUCUUGCUAUUAUCGCUGACCCUGGAUGGACUGACUGGUGUUUCCCAGGACCACAUGCGGGCUCAUUACCAAACAGGCUCCAACCACAUGAUGCUGAACAUCAACCUUUGGUCGACAUUGCUGCUGGGAAUGGGAAUCCUGUUCACUGGGGAGCUCUGGGAGUUCUUGAGCUUUGCUGAAAGGUACCCUGCCAUCAUCUAUAACAUCCUGCUCUUUGGGCUGACCAGUGCCCUGGGUCAGAGCUUCAUCUUUAUGACGGUUGUGUAUUUUGGUCCCCUGACCUGCUCCAUCAUCACUACAACUCGAAAGUUCUUCACAAUUUUGGCCUCUGUGAUCCUCUUCGCCAAUCCCAUCAGCCCCAUGCAGUGGGUGGGCACUGUGCUUGUGUUCCUGGGUCUUGGUCUUGAUGCCAAGUUUGGGAAAGGAGCUAAGAAGACAUCCCACUAGGAAGAGAGAGACUACCUCCACAUCAAGAAUAUUUAAGUUAUUAUCUCAAACAGUGACAUCUCUUGGGAAAAUGGACUUAAUAGGAAUAUGGGACUGAGUUCCAGUCUUUUUUAAUAAAAUAAAAUCAAGCAAAAUCACAUAUUCUAAAAAAUGCACUUGGAUUUUAACAAGACAGAGUGGUGGUUUUUGUUCUUCAUGCCCUGGAGCAGUCUAUGGUAAAUAAAAGAGGGAGGGAAGAGGCAGAGCUGGAUGUUCAUUACCCAGGCUGCUCCUCUCACGGGUGUGGUUAGCAUGGUUGAGUGGGCGAUUCCUCCAAGAACCUGAGGAUUAUAGGGAGGAACUCUGUGAGAUCGCAGAAUUGUGCUAAUGGCUUCUGUUCCGAUGGGUGAGGCUUGUCCCGUUAGAGCUGGUCCCAUUAGAGGACGGGUGGCUGUCCAUUAGAGCCAGAGAAUGUAAAAGUCACUUCCUCUCCUAAAGCUCCUGUGGGCAAAUAUUUCAUUAAAAAAACAAAGUUG